ACUCUCAUUCAUAGAGCCAGCGGGCGCGGGCGGGACGGGCGCCCCGCGGCCGGACCCAGCCAGGGCACCACGCUGCCCGGCCCUGCGCCGCCAGGCACUUCUUUCCGGGGCUCCUAGGGACGCCAGAAGGAAGUCAACCUCUGCUGCUUCUCCUUGGCCUGCGUUGGACCUUCCUUUUUUUGUUGUUUUUUUUUGUUUUUCCCCUUUCUUCCUUUUGAAUUAACUGGCUUCUUGGCUGGAUGUUUUCAACUUCUUUCCUGGCUGCGAACUUUUCCCCAAUUGUUUUCCUUUUACAACAGGGGGAGAAAGUGCUCUGUGGUCCGAGGCGAGCCGUGAAGUUGCGUGUGCGUGGCAGUGUGCGUGGCAGGAUGUGCGUGCGUGUGUAACCCGAGCCGCCCGAUCUGUUUCGAUCUGCGCCGCGGAGCCCUCCCUCAAGGCCCGCUCCACCUGCUGCGGUUACGCGGCGCUCGUGGGUGUUCGUGCCUCGGAGCAGCUAACCGGCGGGUGCUGGGCGACGGUGGAGGAGUAUCGUCUCGCUGCUGCCCGAGUCAGGGCUGAGUCACCCAGCUGAUGUAGACAGUGGCUGCCUUCCGAAGAGUGCGUGUUUGCAUGUGUGUGACUCUGCGGCUGCUCAACUCCCAACAAACCAGAGGACCAGCCACAAACUUAACCAACAUCCCCAAACCCGAGUUCACAGAUGUGGGAGAGCUGUAGAACCCUGAGUGUCAUCGACUGGGCCUUCUUAUGAUUGUUGUUUUAAGAUUAGCUGAAGAUCUCUGAAACGCUGAAUUUUCUGCACUGAGCGUUUUGACAGAAUUCAUUGAGAGAACAGAGAACAUGACAAGUACUUCUAGCUCAGCACUGCUCCAACUACUGAAGCUGAUUUUCAAGGCUACUUAAAAAAAUCUGCAGCGUACAUUAAUGGAUUUCUGUUGUGUUUAAAUUCUCCACAGAUUGUAUUGUAAAUAUUUUAUGAAGUAGAGCAUAUGUAUAUAUUUAUAUAUACGUGCACAUACAUUAGUAGCACUACCUUUGGAAGUCUCAGCUCUUGCUUUUCGGGACUGAAGCCAGUUUUGCAUGAUAAAAGUGGCCUUGUUACGGGAGAUAAUUGUGUUCUGUUGGGACUUUAGACAAAACUCACCUGCAAAAAACUGACAGGCAUUAACUACUGGAACUUCCAAAUAAUGUGUUUGCUGAUCGUUUUACUCUUCGCAUAAAUAUUUUAGGAAGUGUAUGAGAAUUUUGCCUUCAGGAACUUUUCUAACAGCCAAAGACAGAACUUAACCUCUGCAAGCAAGAUUCGUGGAAGAUAGUCUCCACUUUUUAAUGCACUAAGCAAUCGGUUGCUAGGAGCCCAUCCUGGGUCAGAGGCCGAUCCGCAGAACCAGAACGUUUUCCCCUCCUGGACUGUUAGUAACUUAGUCUCCCUCCUCCCCUAACCACCCCCGCCCCCCCCCACCCCCCGCAGUAAUAAAGGCCCCUGAACGUGUAUGUUGGUCUCCCGGGAGCUGCUUGCUGAAGAUCCGCGCCCCUGUCGCCGUCUGGUAGGAGCUGUUUGCAGGGUCCUAACUCAAUCGGCUUGUUGUGAUGCGUAUCCCCGUAGAUGCCAGCACGAGCCGCCGCUUCACGCCGCCUUCCACCGCGCUGAGCCCAGGCAAGAUGAGCGAGGCGUUGCCGCUGGGCGCCCCGGACGCCGGCGCUGCCCUGGCCGGCAAGCUGAGGAGCGGCGACCGCAGCAUGGUGGAGGUGCUGGCCGACCACCCGGGCGAGCUGGUGCGCACCGACAGCCCCAACUUCCUCUGCUCCGUGCUGCCUACGCACUGGCGCUGCAACAAGACCCUGCCCAUCGCUUUCAAGGUGGUGGCCCUAGGGGAUGUUCCAGAUGGCACUCUGGUCACUGUGAUGGCUGGCAAUGAUGAAAACUACUCGGCUGAGCUGAGAAAUGCUACCGCAGCCAUGAAGAACCAGGUUGCAAGAUUUAAUGACCUCAGGUUUGUCGGUCGAAGUGGAAGAGGGAAAAGCUUCACUCUGACCAUCACUGUCUUCACAAACCCACCGCAAGUCGCCACCUACCACAGAGCCAUCAAAAUCACAGUGGAUGGGCCCCGAGAACCUCGAAGACAUCGGCAGAAACUAGAUGAUCAGACCAAGCCCGGGAGCUUGUCCUUUUCCGAGCGGCUCAGUGAACUGGAGCAGCUGCGGCGCACAGCCAUGAGGGUCAGCCCACACCACCCAGCCCCCACGCCCAACCCUCGUGCCUCCCUGAACCACUCCACUGCCUUUAACCCUCAGCCUCAGAGUCAGAUGCAGGAUACAAGGCAGAUCCAACCAUCCCCACCGUGGUCCUACGAUCAGUCCUACCAAUACCUGGGAUCCAUUGCCUCUCCUUCUGUGCACCCAGCAACGCCCAUUUCACCUGGACGUGCCAGCGGCAUGACAACCCUCUCUGCAGAACUUUCCAGUCGACUCUCAACGGCACCCGACCUGACAGCGUUCAGCGACCCGCGCCAGUUCCCCGCGCUGCCCUCCAUCUCCGACCCCCGCAUGCACUAUCCAGGCGCCUUCACCUACUCCCCGACGCCGGUCACCUCGGGCAUCGGCAUCGGCAUGUCGGCCAUGGGCUCGGCCACGCGCUACCACACCUACCUGCCGCCGCCCUACCCCGGCUCGUCGCAAGCGCAGGGAGGCCCGUUCCAAGCCAGCUCGCCCUCCUACCACCUGUACUACGGCGCCUCGGCCGGCUCCUACCAGUUCUCCAUGGUGGGCGGCGAGCGCUCGCCGCCGCGCAUCCUGCCGCCCUGCACCAACGCCUCCACCGGCUCCGCGCUGCUCAACCCCAGCCUCCCGAACCAGAGCGACGUGGUGGAGGCCGAGGGCAGCCACAGCAACUCCCCCACCAACAUGGCGCCCUCCGCGCGCCUGGAGGAGGCCGUGUGGAGGCCCUACUGAGGCGCCAGGCCUGGCCCGGCUGGGCCCCGCGGGCCGCCGCCUUCGCCUCCGGGCGCGCGGGCCUCCUGUUCGCGACAAGCCCGCCGGGAUCCCGGGCCCUGGGCCCGGCCACCGUCCUGGGGCCGAGGGCGCCCGACGGCCAGGAUCUCGCUGUAGGUCAGGCCCGCGCAGCCUCCUGCGCCCAGAAGCCCACGCCGCCGCCGUCUGCUGGCGCCCCGGCCCUCGCGGAGGUGUCCGAGGCGACGCACCUCGAGGGUGUCCGCCGGCCCCAGCACCCAGGGGACGCGCUGGAAAGCAAACAGGAAGAUUCCCGGAGGGAAACUGUGAAUGCUUCUGAUUUAGCAAUGCUGUGAAUAAAAAGAAAGAUUUUAUACCCUUGACUUAACUUUUUAACCAAGUUGUUUAUUCCAAAGAGUGUGGAAUUUUGGUUGGGGUGGGGGGAGAGGAGGGAUGCAACUCGCCCUGUUUGGCAUCUAAUUCUUAUUUUUAAUUUUUCCGCACCUUAUCAAUUGCAAAAUGCGUAUUUGCAUUUGGGUGGUUUUUAUUUUUAUAUACGUUUAUAUAAAUAUAUAUAAAUUGAGCUUGCUUCUUUCUUGCUUUGACCAUGGAAAGAAAUAUGAUUCCCUUUUCUUUAAGUUUUAUUUAACUUUUCUUUUGGACUUUUGGGUAGUUGUUUUUUUUUGUUUUGUUUUGUUUUUUUGAGAAACAGCUACAGCUUUGGGUCAUUUUUAACUACUGUAUUCCCACAAGGAAUCCCCAGAUAUUUAUGUAUCUUGAUGUUCAGACAUUUAUGUGUUGAUAAUUUUUUAAUUAUUUAAAUGUACUUAUAUUAAGAAAAAUAUCAAGUACUACAUUUUCUUUUGUUCUUGAUAGUAGCCAAAGUUAAAUGUAUCACAUUGAAGAAGGCUAGAAAAAAAGAAUGAGUAAUGUGAUCGCUUGGUUAUCCAGAAGUAUUGUUUACAUUAAACUCCCUUUCAUGUUAAUCAAACAAGUGAGUAGCUCACGCAGCAACGUUUUUAAUAGGAUUUUUAGACACUGAGGGUCACUCCAAGGAUCAGAAGUAUGGAAUUUUCUGCCAGGCUCAACAAGGGUCUCAUAUCUAACUUCCUCCUUAAAACAGAGAAGGUCAAUCUAGUUCCAGAGGGUUGAGGCAGGUGCCAAUAAUUACAUCUUUGGAGAGGAUUUGAUUUCUGCCCAGGGAUUUGCUCACCCCAAGGUCAUCUGAUAAUUUCACAGAUGCUGUGUAACAGAACACAGCCAAAGUAAACUGUGUAGGGGAGCCACAUUUACAUAGGAACCAAAUCAAUGAAUUUAGGGGUUACGAUUAUAGCAAUUUAAGGGCCCACCAGAAGCAGGCCUCGAGGAGUCAAUUUGCCUCUGUGUGCCUCAGUGGAGACAAGUGGGAAAACAUGGUCCCACCUGUGCGAGACCCCCUGUCCUGUGCUGCUCACUCAACAACAUCUUUGUGUUGCUUUCACCAGGCUGAGACCCUACCCUAUGGGGUAUAUGGGCUUUUACCUGUGCACCAGUGUGACAGGAAAGAUUCAUGUCACUACUGUCCGUGGCUACAAUUCAAAGGUAUCCAAUGUCGCUGUAAAUUUUAUGGCACUAUUUUUAUUGGAGGAUUUGGUCAGAAUGCAGUUGUUGUACAACUCAUAAAUACUAACUGCUGAUUUUGACACAUGUGUGCUCCAAAUGAUCUGGUGGUUAUUUAACGUACCUCUUAAAAUUCGUUGAAACGAUUUCAGGUCAACUCUGAAGAGUAUUUGAAAGCAGGACUUCAGAACAGUGUUUGAUUUUUAUUUUAUAAAUUUAAGCAUUCAAAUUAGGCAAAUCUUUGGCUGCAGGCAGCAAAAACAGCUGGACUUAUUUAAAACAACUUGUUUUUGAGUUUUCUUAUAUAUAUAUUGAUUAUUUGUUUUACACACAUGCAGUAGCACUUUGGUAAGAGUUAAAGAGUAAAGCAGCUUAUGUUGUCAGGUCGUUCUUAUCUAGAGAAGAGCUAUAGCAGAUCUCGGACAAACUCAGAAUAUAUUCACUUUCAUUUUUGACAGGAUUCCCUCCACAACUCAGUUUCAUAUAUUAUUCCGUAUUACAUUUUUGCAGCUAAAUUACCAUAAAAUGUCAGCAAAUGUAAAAAUUUAAUUUCUGAAAAGCACCAUUAGCCCAUUUCCCCCAAAUUAAACGUAAAUGUUUUUUUUCAGCACAUGUUACCAUGUCUGACCUGCAAAAAUGCUGGAGAAAAAUGAAGGAAAAAAUUAUGUUUUUCAGUUUAAUUCUGUUAACUGAAGAUAUUCCAACUCAAAACCAGCCUCAUGCUCUGAUUAGAUAAUCUUUUACAUUGAACCUUUACUCUCAAAGCCAUGUGUGGAGGGGGCUUGUCACUAUUGUAGGCUCACUGGAUUGGUCAUUUAGAGUUUCACAGACUCUUACCAGCAUAUAUAGUAUUUAAUUGUUUCAAAAAAAAUCAAACUGUAGUUGUUUUGGCGAUAGGUCUCACGCAACACAUUUUUGUAUGUGUGUGUGUGUGCGUGUGUGUGUGUGUGUGUGAAAAAUUGCAUUCAUUGACUUCAGGUAGAUUAAGGUAUCUUUUUAUUCAUUGCCCUCAGGAAAGUUAAGGUAUCAAUGAGACCCUUAAGCCAAUCAUGUAAUAACUGCAUGUGUCUGGUCCAGGAGAAGUAUUGAAUAAGCCAUUUCUACUGCUUACUCAUGUCCCUAUUUAUGAUUUCAACAUGGAUACAUAUUUCAGUUCUUUCUUUUUCUCACUAUCUGAAAAUACAUUUCCCUCCCUCUCUUCCCCCCAAUAUCUCCCUUUUUUUCUCUCUUCCUCUAUCUUCCAAACCCCACUUUCUCCCUCCUCCUUUUCCUGUGUUCUCUUAAGCAGAUAGCACAUACCCCCACCCAGUACCAAAUUUCAGAACACAAGAAGGUCCAGUUCUUCCCCCUUCACAUAAAGGAACAUGGUUUGUCAGCCUUUCUCCUGUUUAUGGGUUUCUUCCAGCAGAACAGAGACAUUGCCAACCAUAUUGGAUCUGCUUGCUGUCCAAACCAGCAAACUUUCCUGGGCAAAUCACAAUCAGUGAGUAAAUAGACAGCCUUUCUGCUGCCUUGGGUUUCUGUGCAGAUAAACAGAAAUGCUCUGAUUAGAAAGGAAAUGAAUGGUUCCACUCAAAUGUCCUGCAAUUUAGGAUUGCAGAUUUCUGCCUUGAAAUACCUGUUUCUUUGGGACAUUCCGUCCUGAUGAUUUUUAUUUUUGUUGGUUUUUAUUUUUGGGGGGAAUGACAUGUUUGGGUCUUUUAUACAUGAAAAUUUGUUUGACAAUAAUCUCACAAAACAUAUUUUACAUCUGAACAAAAUGCCUUUUUGUUUACCGUAGCGUAUACAUUUGUUUUGGGAUUUUUGUGUGUUUGUUGGGAAUUUUGUUUUUAGCCAGGUCAGUAUUGAUGAGGCUGAUCAUUUGGCUCUUUUUUUCCUUCCAGAAGAGUUGCAUCAACAAAGUUAAUUGUAUUUAUGUAUGUAAAUAGAUUUUAAGCUUCAUUAUAAAAUAUUGUUAAUGCCUAUAACUUUUUUUCAAUUUUUUUGUGUGUGUUUCUAAGGACUUUUUCUUAGGUUUGCUAAAUACUGUAGGGAAAAAAAUGCUUCUUUCUACUUUGUUUAUUUUAGACUUUAAAAUGAGCUACUUCUUAUUCACUUUUGUAAACAGCUAAUAGCAUGGUUCCAAUUUUUUUUAAGUUCACUUUUUUUGUUCUAGGGGAAAUGAAUGUGCAAAAAAAGAAAAAGAACUGUUGGUUAUUUGUGUUAUUCUGGAUGUAUAAAAAUCAAUGGAAAAAAAUAAACUUUCAAAUUGAAAUGACGGUAUAACACAUCUACUGAAAAAGCAACGGGAAAUGUGGUCCUAUUUAAGCCAGCCCCCACCUAGGGUCUAUUUGUGUGGCAGUUAUUGGGUUUGGUCACAAAACAUCCUGAAAAUUCGUGCGUGGGCUUCUUUCUCCCUGGUACAAACGUAUGGAAUGCUUCUUAAAGGGGAACUGUCAAGCUGGUGUCUUCAGCCAGAUGACAUGAGAGAAUAUCCCAGAACCCUCUCUCCAAGGUGUUUCUAGAUAGCACAGGAGAGCAGGCACUGCACUGUCCACAGUCCACGGUACACAGUCGGGUGGGCCGCCUCCCCUCUCCUGGGAGCAUUCGUCGUGCCCAGCCUGAGCAGGGCAGCUGGACUGCUGCUGUUCAGGAGCCACCAGAGCCUUCCUCUCUUUGUACCACAGUUUCUUCUGUAAAUCCAGUGUUACAAUCAGUGUGAAUGGCAAAUAAACAGUUUGACAAGUACAUACACCAUA